GGUCUCCGCUCAACGAUCCUUCCUCAAAGCAUGGUUGCUGAGUACCCAGAGUUGCGAGGAGUUUUUUAACUGAUUUAGCCAGGUGGCAAUCAUGAGUGAAUGGAUGAAGAAAGGCCCCUUAGAAUGGCAAGAUUACAUUUACAAAGAGGUCCGAGUGACAGCCAGUGAGAAGAAUGAGUAUAAAGGAUGGGUUUUAACUACAGACCCAGUCUCUGCCAAUAUUGUCCUUGUGAACUUCCUUGAAGAUGGCAGCAUGUCUGUGACCGGAAUUAUGGGACAUGCUGUGCAGACUGUUGAAACUAUGAAUGAAGGGGACCAUAGAGUGAGGGAGAAGCUGAUGCAUUUGUUCACGUCUGGAGACUGCAAAGCAUACAGCCCAGAGGAUCUGGAAGAGAGAAAGAACAGCCUAAAGAAAUGGCUUGAGAAGAACCACAUCCCCAUCACUGAACAGGGAGACGCUCCAAGGACUCUCUGUGUGGCUGGGGUCCUGACUAUAGACCCACCAUAUGGUCCAGAAAAUUGCAGCAGCUCUAAUGAGAUUAUUCUGUCGCGUGUUCAGGAUCUUAUUGAAGGACAUCUUACAGCUUCCCAAUGAGAGGCCAGGAAGUGUGAACAUACUGAUAGAAAAAGACUAUAUUUUAUCCCUCAUAAAAUGUUUUAAAUGUAAAUGUACAUGACUGUGUGUGUGUAUGUGUGUGUGUGUAUAAUUCUUUGUUGUUUUGGUAAAAUCAGAGGAGUGGGUUAUAAGUGCUAAUUUCCUUGGGAAAUUAAUGAACUAGGGCAAGUAUAGCAUCCCAUGCAUAAAAUUAGCACAGGGACAUCAGAAUUGUAUGGGUCUUCUUUUUUCUUUUUUUCUUUUUUUUUUGAGAUGGAGUCUCGCUCUGUUGCCAGGUUUGAGUGCAGUGGCGCAAUCUCAGCUCAGUGCAACCUCCGCCUCCCAGGUUCAACCGAUUCCCCUGCCUCAGCCUCUCGAGUAGCUGGGACUACAGGUGCACGCCACCACUCCCAGCUAAUUUUUUGUAUUUUAGUAGAGAUGGGGUUUCACCUGUAUGGGUCUUUUCUUGUGAUGGGGUUACACCCCCAUUUUUGUUAGGCAAGAAAAGCAUUUGGAAAAAAAUGUAACAUGUUAGAUUCAAUAUAAAAUAUUAUGGUAAGAUCAUGGUCUUGUUAAGUCUCUUCACUAACUGUAUGUGUCUGUUUUUAAAAGAUGUGUCUUGGUGGGGCGCGGUGGCUCACGCCUGUAAUCCCAGCACUUUGGGAGGCCGAGGCAGGUGGAUCAUGAGGUCAGGAGAUCGAGACCAUCCUGGCUAACACGGUGAAACCCCUUCUCUACUAAAAAUACAAAAAAAAUUAGCCGGGCGUGGUGGCAGGUGCCUGUAGUCCCAGCUACUCAGGAGGCUGAGGCAGGAGAAUGGCAUGAACCCGGGAGGCAGAGCUUGCAGUGAGCCGAGAUCGCGCCACUGCACUCUAGCCUGGGUGACAGAGCGAGACUCCGUCUCAAAAAAAAAAAAAAAAAUUAUUGGAACACAGCAUUACCUAUUGAAUUACAGUUUUCUGGUUUUUUUGUGGAGUUUUUGUUUUGGUUUUUGAGAUGGAGUUUCACUCUUGUUCCCCAGGCUGGAGUGUAAUAGUGCAAUCUCGGCUUACCACAACCUCUGCCUCCCAGGUUCAAGCAAUUCUCCUGCCUCAGCCUCCUGAGUAGCUGGUAUUACAGGCAUGCACCAUCACGCCCCACUAAUUUUGUAUUUUUUUAGUAGAGACGGGGUUUUUCCAUGUUGGUCAGGCUGGUCUCAAACUCCCGACCUCAGGUGAUCCGCCCGCCUCGGCCUCCCAAAGUUCUGGGAUUACAGGUGUGAGCCACCGUGCCCGGCUGUUUUUUGUGGGUUUUUUGUUUGUUUGUUUGUUUUUGAGACAGAGUCUUGCUCUGUCACUCAGGCUGGAGUGCAGUGGCACAAUCUCGGCUCACUGCAACCUCUGCCUCCUGAGUUCAAGCCAUUCUCCUGCCUCAGCCCCCUCAGUAGCUGGGAUUACCAGGCACAUAGCACCAUGCCCAGCUAAUGUUUGUAUUUUUAGUAGAGACAGGGUUUCACCAUGUUGACCAGGCUGGUCUUGAACUCCUGACCUCAUGAUCUGCCUGCCGUGGCCUCCCAAAGUGCUGGGAUUAUAGGCAUGAGAGCCUCCGUGCCUGGCUUUUUUUUUUUUUUUUUUUUUUUAAAAGAGGGUCUUGAUAUGUUGCCCAGGCUUGUCUUCAACUCCUGGGUUCAAGUGAUCCUUCCACCUUGGCCUCCCAAAGUGCUGGGAAUAUAGGUGUGAGCUGCCAUGUCCAGCUGUAAGAAAUAUUUUAAAAUAUUUAAGCUUCAGGGCCUUUGAAUACAGGCCCUGAUAACAUAGCUAUUUUCCUGCAUAGUUGUCUAAUAACAAGAUGGUAUAGCCCAGUGCUUCUUGCACUUUAGCAAGCAUCAGAAUCAGCAAAUAUUUAGGUUUCAGGGCCUUUGAAUACAGUCUGAUAACACAGCUAUUUUCCUGCAUAGUUGUCUAAUAACAAGAUGGUAUAGUCCAGUGCUUCCUGCAUGUUGGCAAGCAUCAGAAUCAGCUGCAGGGCUUUUCAAAACAGAUUGCUGGACCCUCCUCCCAACAGAUUCUGAUUCAGUAGUUCUAGUUGGGACCCAGGAAUUUGCAUUUCCAACAGACUCCCAGAUAAUGAUGUUACCGUUCCCAGACCACACUUGCAGAAGCAGUUCAGAAACUUCAGGGGAACAGAAAGUUCCUCCCUCACGGCUUCAAAGUUCCAUGAUCCUGAAAGCAAAAUUUAGCACACAUCACCUUUCUCCUAGUGGCUAAGACUCUCCUGUUCAAACCCUGGAUGUCUUCAGAAAGCAAAUAGAAGGGGAAUAUGAACAGACUGAAGUCAGCAAGGAAAUGACUGACAAGAUGAGGGAGGCCUUUGAAAAGGAAGAAGCCAGCUGGGCGCGGUGGCUCACGCCUGUAAUCCCAGCACUUUGGGAGGCCUAGGCGGGCCGAUCACUUGAGGCCAGGAUUUGUGACCAACCUGGGCAACAUGGUGAAACCCUGUCUCUACUAAAAAAAAAAAAAAUAGCUGGGUGUGGUGGUGAGCGCCUAUAAUCUCAGCUACUCAGGAGGCUGAGGCACUCGCUUGAAUCUGGGAGGUGGAGGUUGCAGUGAGCCGAGAUUGUACGCAUUCCAGCUUGGGCAGCAGAACGAGACUCUGUCUCAAAAAAAAAAAAAAAGCCACGUAGGAAAUUAUCCACAGCAUCAAUUGGACUUGAUCUUGGCUCAGGGACCAGGCCCGGUGCCUUGAUAUUGGUAGAUUUAUUUGCCAUCAGACUAAUGAGCUGGGGACAUUGACUGUUUCCUGGCAACUGAGUCCUCUGAUUGUGUAAACAAUUUGCCUGCAAACAAAACCUGAGUGCUUGAAAGGGUAAGUGAUCCUGAUCUGCCAUAGAAACCUUCAUGCUUAGGGAGUUUCCCUAGCUAAUUCCUCAGCUAAGAUUCUCCCCAGGAGUUUCACUCACCUGUUUCCAGUGCCUCCUUUGGGCUGUCAGCAUCUGUGAUUCCACAUUCCCCAGAGGGAGAUUCCUCCCCAAAGCUGGUUGUAUUUACUGCCAGUCCUGGGCUGUAGCCAGGGCAGUCUUUGAACACAUUAUCAAGAAUACUUUUUAAAAUAAAAGUCUGUUUCGACUUCCA